AGAGCGGCUCAGAGACAGGAGGCGGCGGCAGCAGCGGCGGCAUGAACCACUGCCAGCUACCGGUGGUGAUCGACAACGGCUCGGGAAUGAUCAAGGCGGGCGUGGCUGGGUGCCGGGAGCCCCAGUUUAUCUACCCGAACAUUAUCGGCCGCGCCAAGGGCCAGAGCCGCGCGGCCCAGGGCGGGCUAGAACUCUGCGUGGGCGACCAAGCUCAGGACUGGAGGAGCUCGCUGUUCAUCAGUUACCCAGUGGAGCGUGGUCUCAUUACUUCAUGGGAGGACAUGGAGAUCAUGUGGAAGCAUAUCUAUGACUAUAACCUAAAGCUGAAGCCGUGUGAUGGCCCAGUCUUGAUUACUGAGCCAGCGCUGAACCCACUGGCCAACCGGCAACAGAUCACGGAAAUGUUUUUUGAGCAUCUGGGUGUUCCUGCCUUCUAUAUGUCCAUCCAGGCUGUGCUGGCUCUCUUUGCUGCUGGCUUCACUACUGGCCUUGUGCUGAAUUCAGGUGCUGGGGUUACCCAGAGUGUGCCCAUCUUUGAGGGUUACUGUCUGCCUCAUGGUGUGCAGCAACUGGAUCUGGCAGGCCUUGACCUCACCAACUACCUCAUGGUGCUAAUGAAGAACCAUGGUAUCAUGUUGCUCAGUGCUUCAGACAGAAAGAUUGUUGAAGACAUCAAGGAGAGCUUUUGUUAUGUGGCAAUGAACUACGAAGAGGAAAUGGCCAAGAAACCCGAUUGUCUAGAGAAAGUUUACCAACUACCUGAUGGGAAGGUCAUCCAGCUCCAUGACCAGCUCUUUUCUUGUCCAGAGGCCCUCUUCUCUCCGUGUCAUAUGAACCUUGAGGCCCCUGGCAUUGAUAAGAUAUGCUUCAGCAGCAUAAUGAAAUGUGAUACAGGCCUGAGGAAUUCCUUCUUUUCCAAUAUUAUCCUUGCCGGGGGAUCAACCUCUUUCCCUGGUUUAGACAAGCGGUUAGUUAAGGAUAUAGCAAAGGUGGCUCCUGCCAACACCGCUGUGCAAGUUAUAGCUCCUCCAGAAAGGAAAAUAUCAGUGUGGAUGGGAGGUUCUAUUCUUGCAUCCUUGUCUGCCUUCCAGGACAUGUGGAUCACUGCUGCAGAAUUUAAAGAAGUUGGACCCAACAUAGUACACCAAAGAUGCUUCUGAAAUACAGAUAAAAUGGUUGGAAGAAAAUGUUUUGAGUAUAUGUGACAGAAAACUUUGGAUAUUAUAUGUUUCUGGGAGAAGAGAAAAUACUUCACCUAUUGGGAUGCCAAUAUUUCUGUUGUAUUUCUAUAAUGGGUUUGGGGGAUAAUAAUGGUGAAGCUCAAGAACAGAUGUCUAUUGAGUAGAACCAAGUUAAAAUAAUGUUUCCCAUAGUGUUUCUUCUAUAACUUGACGUUGGUGAGCUUAUAUUUCCCUUGGAAGAGAGCAUUUGUGGUACAAUAUGCUAUGUGCCAAAUGAGUGAUAAGAUUUAAGCUUAUUGAAGUUUAGGGAAAGAAGGUUGCUGUGGUGAGGAACGAGACUCCAUAGCAGAGGUAUGCCAUCAUGGAAGGGGUGGCAUUGGGAUGGAGCGCAGAUAUCCAGGCAAGCAUACUAAAAUGAACAAGUUGCUAAAGAUGAGAAUGAACAAAGCAUAUUCAGGGCAUGUUUAAUAGACUGAUUUUGUUUUUAAAA